CCGCUGGCUAGACCAUGGAGGGCCGCUGGGUGCAGCCACAGAGCGCGGGGCCCCGGCGACCCCGCCCCGCUCCGCGUCACUCGGCGCCCUGCGGCGCGCGAUGAGCACCUACCACUAGCGGAGCCGCGAGGGAGAGGCCGCGGCCCCUUCCCGUUGCCUGCGGCCACCGGCCGGCAUUCAGAGCCCCUCGCCUGGCGCUAAAUUUAAAAACGUAACACGAGCAGCAGGCUGGUCUCGGAAACGAAACGAAAUUCGGUCCCUGGGCCUCCUCCCGGGCGCUGCCGGUCCCUCAGCGCGCCGCGCCACCCGGAACAGACCCUUCUCCCGCCAUUUUCGGCGGGGCUGGGAGACUGAGGCCCGCGGCGCUGAGCCUGCGGCGCCCCGGAAGAGGCGGGCGGCAUGGCCGCUGGCGUGGACUGCGGGGACGGGGUUGGCGCCCGGCAGCACGUGUUCCUGGUUUCAGAAUAUUUAAAAGAUGCUUCAAAGAAGAUGAAAAAUGGGCUAAUGUUUGUAAAACUGGUUAACCCCUGUUCAGGAGAAGGAGCCAUUUACUUGUUCAAUAUGUGUCUACAGCAGCUGUUUGAAGUAAAAGUUUUCAAGGAAAAACACCAUUCUUGGUUUAUAAAUCAAUCAGUUCAAUCAGGAGGUCUUCUCCAUUUUGCCACACCUGUGGAUCCUCUAUUUCUGCUUCUCCACUACCUCAUAAAGGCUGAUAAGGAGGGGAAGUUUCAGCCCCUUGAUCAAGUUGUGGUGGAUAACGUGUUUCCAAAUUGCAUCUUGUUGCUGAAACUUCCUGGACUUGAGAAGUUACUUCAUCAUGUGACAGAGGAAAAAGGUAAUCCAGAAAUAGACAACAAGAAAUAUUACAAGUACAGCAAAGAGAAGACAUUAAAGUGGCUGGAAAAAAAGGUUAAUCAAACUGUGGCAGCAUUAAAAACCAAUAAUGUGAAUGUCAGUUCCCGGGUACAGUCAACUGCAUUUUUCUCUGGUGACCAAGCUUCCACUGACAAGGAAGAGGAUUAUAUUCGUUAUGCCCAUGGUCUGAUAUCUGACUACAUCCCUAAAGAAUUAAGUGAUGACUUAUCUAAAUACUUAAAGCUUCCAGAACCUUCAGCCUCAUUGCCAAAUCCUCCAUCAAAGCUAGGUCUACCAACUGGUCAUUUUGUGAAGAGCUAGUGGGAGACCCUUCAAGCUGACUUGUGUAUCUUUUGGGUAUGUUUCUAUCAUUCUUUAAUACAUUCCUGCUUCUGCGACUGGAGUUUCAGCCUCUUGUCCUGUGCAAGCCCUGAAUCCACCUUUUUUUCAAAGAACCCUGGUUCCUUUCAGUGAAGAAUGGUAUUUAGAAACCAAGAUCUAGGCAGUAGGUAUGCUCAUUGCUAUUGGUAUGUCAUUGCUUAGGAGCCAAAGCUAGGAAAUGUGUGUGUGUGUACAACAUGUACACACACAUAUAUACACUAUAUACUCGUAUCAACAUUUCUAAAUCUAUCCAUGUAUCUAUCAGUAUUUAUCUAUGUGUGUGGUUUUUUGUAGAUUCCCUUUAUCAGGCUGAGAAAGUUUCCUUCUGUUCCUAGUUCACUGAGAGUUUUUAUCAUAUAUAGGUAUUUAUCAUAUGUGGAUAUUGUCAAAUAAUUUGUAUCUACUGAGAUGAUCAAGUAGUUUUCUUUUUAAUAGAGGAAUGUCUUUUAAUAUAUGAAUUAUAAUGAUUGAUUUUUGAAUGUUAAACUAAUUUUGCAUUCUUGAGAUAAUCCCUACUUGGUCACAGUAUAUUAUUCUUUUUAUAUGUAGUAUGGGGUUUUUUUCCUAAUAUUUUGUUAAGUACUUUUUUGUAUCUCUGUUCAUGAGGGAUAUUGGUCUGUGGUUUUCUUUACUUGUAAUGAUUUUGUCUGAUUUUGAUGUCAGAGUAAAACUGGGCUUAUAAAAUGAGUUGGGAAGUAUUCUUUCAUCACUUAUUUUCUGAAAGAGUUUGUGUGAGGUUGGUGUUGUUGCUUCCUUAUAUGUCGGACACAAUUCACCAGUGAAGCCAUUUGGACCUGGAAUUUUCUUUGGGGGAAACUUUUAAAUUACUAAUUCAAUUUCUAUAAUAGAUGAAGAGCUAUUCUAAUUUUCUUUUUUUUUCUUGUGCCAGUUUUGGUAAUUUAUGUCUUUCAAGAAAUGUAUCCAUUUGAUCUAGGUUGUCAAAUUUAUUGGCAUAAGUUGUUCAUCACAUUUUUAUUAUCCUUUUAAUGUCUGUGGAUCUGUAGUGAUAUUCCCUUUUUCAUACCUGAUGUUGGUCAUCUGUGUCUUCUUUUUGCUUUCUCUGUUAGUAUAGCUAAAGGUUUGUCAAUUUCAUUGAUCCUUUCAAAGAAUCAUUGUCUUCUGGCUUGCAUAAUCUCUGAUGAGACAUCUAUGAUAUUUCUUAUAUUUCUUCUCCUUUACAUAAUGUGUCUCCUCCUCAUGGGUUCUUUUAAGAUUUUCUUCUUUAUUACUAGUUUUCAGCAAGUUGACUAUGAUGUGUUGAUGUGGUUUUCUUUUUGUUUAUCUCAUUUGGGAGUGUAUUAAGCUCCUUGAACUUUUGAGUUUUUAAUUUUCAUCAAAUAUGGAAAAUUUCUGGCCAAUAUUUCUUUAAAUACCUUUUUCCAUUCUUUCCUCCCUUUUCUCCCUAUCCCCUCAGCUUCUGGCCUCCAAUUUCAUGUAUGCUGGAACACUUGGUAUUGUCCUCCAGGUCCUAUCACUGAGUUUCUGUUUUGUUGGUUGUUUGUUUUUUUAUGUUCCAUUUUUAGACAGUUUCUAGGUGUAUCUUCAAGUUUACUUUGAUUUAUAGCAUUUCAUCUUCUGUUAACCUUAGUUAUUUAAUUUUUACUUUAAAUAUUGUAAUUUUAUUUAUUUAUUUAUUUAUUUUUGAGAUGGAGUUUCGCUCUUGUUGCCCAGGCUGGAGUGCAAUGGCACAAUCUCAGCUCGCUGCAACUUCCGCCUCCCGGGUUCAAGUGAUUCACCUGCCUCAGCCUCCCAAGUAGCUGGGAUUACAGUCAUGCGUCACCAGACCUGGCUAAUUUUGUAUUUUUAGUAGAGAUGGGGUUUCUCCAUGUUGGUCAGGCUGGUCUUGAACUCCCGACCUCAGGUGAUCCGCCCACCUCAGCCUCCCAAAGUGCUGGGAUUACAGGCCUGAGCCACCACGCCCGGCCUUAAAUAUUGUAAUUUUUAGUUCUAGACGUUCCAUUUGGUUCUUCUUUAUGUCUUCCCGUAUCUGUUCUUAUUAUGCUUGCAGUUUUCUUUAAAUACUUCAAUAUAGUUAAAAUAGCUACUUAAAUGUCCUCAUUUGCUAGUUCUAUUAUCUUUGUUAUUUUCUAUCUUCUAGGUCUAUUUUUCUCCUCUCUCUUUUACUUUAUUUUGAAAUAAUUUUAUACUUUUCUAGAAAAGUCACAAAAAUAGUAGAGUUUAGAUAUGAUGUUCACCCAGCUUCCCUCAGUAUUAGCAUACAUGACCAUACUACAAAGAUCAAAACCAGAAAAUUUACCUUAUUGUACUUUCACCUAUCUUUCCACUAAUACUUUUUUAAUUUCAGAAUUCAGUCUGUGAUGGUACAUUGCAUUUAGCUGCCACAUCUCUUCAGUGUUUUCUAAUUUGUAAGAGUCCCGGCCGGGUGCGUUGGCUCACGCCUGUAAUCCCAGCACUUUGGGAGGCCAGGGCGGGCAGAUCACCUGAGGUCAGGAGUUUGAGAUAAGCCUGACCAACAUGGAGAAACCCCAUCUCUACUAAAAAUACAAAACAUUAGCCAGACAUGGUGGCACAUGCCUGUAAUCCCAGCUACUCGGGAGGCUGAGGCAGGAGAAUCACUUGAACCCAGGAGGUGGAGGUUGCAGUGAGCCGAGAUCACACCACUGCACUCCAGUCUGGGCAGUAAGAGGAAACUCCAUCUCAAAAUAAAAAAAAGAGUCCCUCAAUAUUCCUUUGUCUUUCAAUGACCUUGACACUUUUGAGAGUAGUAGCCAGUUUUUUUAUAAAUGCCCCUUAAUUUUUGAGAUACUUUGAAACUAUGUUAAUAUCCUAUUUCUUUUACGAUCAUUUCACUAUACUACUAACUAAUAAUACUGACAAACACUGUAUAGCAUUUAUGUGCUUGGCAUUGAUCUAAGCACUUUACAUAUAAUAACUCAUUUAAUCCCUACAAAAAUUAUAAUCAUAGAGUGCCAUACGAGCCAGAAUAGUGACACCCACCCAAAGCUCAAAAGAUGAGAGGAGGAGCUGCUUAAACACUUGCAUUAUUAUCCCUGUUGAAAGUUAGCUUCUUCACAAUAGGAACUCUGUACCAUUCAAGCUUGUGUCUUGCACGGUGCCGAGCACACAGUAUGCAAUUGGUAAAGGAUGAGUACAUGAUAGUCAGACAGGUUGAAUAAUCUCAGCAAUAUUCUCACUAAUUGAGACUUGAUUGUUUUUUCCAGCAAAGUCGAGAUCUUUAUCUACCUUUAAAGUGCCUAAGCUGUUUUCUGGGUUUCUUUUGGGUCCUUGAAUAUGCCAAGCUGUUUCCACACUGGUGCCUUUGUAUGACUGGUUUGUCUCUAUGUGCCUUUUUCUGAAUCUUCACAGGACUGGCUCCAUCUUGUUAUUAUCACUUAUCUUAAUCACUUUUCCAGAGACCCAAUCCUUGACCUUCCUCCCCUACCCCCACCCAGCUCCUACUCAGUACUCUCCAUACCAUUUUCCUGCCUUACUCCCUGCAUAGGACCUUGCCUGACUGCUUCACAUAUAGUCAUGCCCCGCACAGCAAUGGUUUGAUUGAUGGCAGACUGCAUAUGCGAUGGUGGUCCCAUGAGACUAUAACACAGAGCUGAAAAAUUCCUAUCACCUAGUGAGUUGUAGCCAUCAUAACGUAAGGUUGUAGCACAUUGCAUUACCUUUUAUAUGUUUAAAUAAGUUUAGAUAUACAAGUACUUACUAUUGUUUUACAGUUGCCUACAGUAUUCAGUACACUAACAUGCUAUACAGGUUUGUACCCCAGGAGCAGUAGGCUGUACCAUAUAGCCAAGGUGUGUAGCAGACUACACCAUAGGUCUGUAUAAGUUGUAUAAGUACACUCUGUGAUGUUCACACAACAACGAAAUUGCUUAGCAACACUUUUCCCAUAACAUAUCCCAUCAUUAAGCAACACAUGACUGUACAUACACAGCACCUAACUUGGGGUUGCAUACAGUAGACCUUCAACAGAUGUUUGUUGCAUGAGAGAAUUAACCAACCAACCAAUCCAUCAAUCCAUCCUGGACACCCCAGACAGGUGUUCAGCAAUACAGUGUUGGAGUCCUUGACAGCCUUGUGGCUAAACCUUGAACUUCAAGAGUCGUUCUGAGAAUGAGUUUUCUGUGAUGCAUUAGUAUUUGAAGUCCAAGGACUUAUUCAUAAACUCACUCAUAAACUUGUAUGGGCCUUAAAUUUGUGUGUUAAUGUUGCUGGUAAUAAAUGAAAUAGAUACAGUCUUUAAUCUCUCUGGAUAAAGGGCUGUGAAUUUUCUUCUGUCAGUUGAUUGAACUGCACUUACUGGAGUCAUUUUACGUAGCAUUUAGAGAUUAUUUAUAUUAAGCCCGCAACCUAAAUUAUUGCAGUUUGAGAAUAUAUGUGGUUUUUAUAAACUCUUUGUAUUCACAGAGGCUUGAAUAGGAGCUCAUAUUAUGAUUUAGCUACAAAUUAUUUGGGAAUUUGGUAAACUGGCAAUUUUGUUUUCUUGCCUGUUUCACUUUACCUUUGAUGCCAAGUUGAAGAUCUCACUGGCAAUGUACAACAUAACUGAGCUGAAUAAUAAUUGAAAAGUGAAAAACAAAAGGUAUUACACAUACCAGGUGCCAUUUUGGGGAAUAAUAUUAGGAAUAAAUCCAUGUGGGUUUAUAGUUAUACAUAAAAUGUUCAUAUACACACAUAACACACAUAAACACACAUAUAUACACAUAAGUACACACAAACAUAAAUGCAUACCCACAUAUGGCACAGAUACAGACUUAAAUCUACAUAGCCUGUCCUUUAGAAUUCUUUAAGGAAUUUCAGACUAGAGCCUUUUUAGACUCUUGUACUAAACAUUAGGAUACGCUAGCCUACUUGAAUCCUUUGGCCCUUUGCUUCUCUUACUUACAUCAUUUUUCUCUUUGAUUAAUGUGCCAAGUUUGGGAAAGCUUCACAACAUUUCCACAAACUGCAAAACCACUUGGGUACAUAGACAAAAGCCUCCAUCUUUUUCAUCAAGCCAUAUAUUUUUUUUUUUCUGAAACUGAUCACAGGUUGCCAACAUUCUUUUUUAUUUCUAGUUUAUCUUCAAUUUAAAUUUACCUUGUAGUCUCAGACCCUGUCAUCUUUCAAGGUUUGUGCUUCUCGGUUCUGCACUGCCAAAGAGACUCUCCUCUGUAAGGCUUAAAUUGGAUGUCAAGUGGAAUUGUCUUUUGUUUGUUCGAAUCUGUUUCAUAUUGUGCUGCUGUCCAUUCCCAAAAUCAUAUUUCUCUUAUUUGGGGCCUUAGCAAGACACAAAGGCAAGCUCUAAGUGAGAACCUAAAGUGUACCUGUUUUCUUACUAAAUGUACAGUGUUGUUUAUAUUGUAUGCAAACUUCUGACAACAGUGAACAAAUAUCUUAAUCUUUAAAAAUAUAAAUAAAGUGAAAAAAGGACUUCACAUCAACCAUGUUUCAGUACUAAACAGACUAAUUAAUACAACAUGGCAGGAUUGUUCCUGGUUGUAGUCUCAGUUCCGCCUUAAUUCUGUGAGCCAUGGAGGAAGUCAUUGGCAUCUCUGGCCCCCAGUCACUUCUCAGCAUGAAAUGGGACUAUAUCAUCAAGAUUUUUUAUGUCUUUCCCUCCAGCCGCUGGUGCUUGGGGAGCCAUGUCUCCUUUACACCUGGGAGGAAAGUGCUUUUAGAGUUAUCUUUCAUGCAGUGCUUACCAUGCACUAGGCACUCCCCUAAACUCUUUAGAUGAACCAGCUCAUGUGUUUUGCUGGAAGAAAGUCUGGAAGAAAAUACAACAAAAUGCUCAUACUGGGUUUUGGGGUGCCCAUGAUAUGUGUAUAUGUAUAUUUCUUUUCUUCAUUUUUCAAAGAUUAUUUCACUUUGCCAUAGAAAGAAAUACAAAGAACACAAUUGUUGGAAAGUAAUAACAAAGACUGGCAAAGCGCAUUGUGAUUUUUAAAGCAACUUUGACAUGAAUUUAUGUGUUUAAUCUUUCCAGGAGCCAUAUGGCACAAAGGGUAUUAUUUCUCUUGUUUUGCAGUUGAACAAGGGAAGGUCAGCUCAUUUCCCCAACAUCACACAGCUAAUGAGUAACUGAGCCAGAACUUGAAUUCAGGACCUCUCACAUCCAGACUCUACCACAUCAAAUUCCCUUUCCCCAGUGGCUCUAACUUUGACUCUGUUACAUCCUAGAACAUCACCUCUUUACCAGAUAUGAAAGACAACCUUUUCACAUAGUUUAGGAGUUGACUUUCUCUGUUCUUAAAGCUGAUCUAACUUGACUAGCUGCCUUGUAUUACAUAUUUUCUCCCAAACACCCCUUUCUCUAGGACGAAUCCAAAAUUUGGCAAUCUUGGGAGUUAGCUAUGUCAUAGUCAGAUCUCUUGGAAGACAAAGAGCUCCAGGUCUAGAGAAGCAAGUGGGAGGGUGUUUUCCAAGUGUACUUAGAAAAUGUUUAUGAGCUUUGUCCUCAUCUGAAUAAUCAGAAGAUAUGAUUUGAUUUUUACACCUUGGUAUACACUUGGAGAUUACACAGUCCUGAGGUUUAUAUAUUCCUCAGAGCCAUUAGACUGACCAAAAGGGUUCGUCCCUGUGUUUCAUAGUAUUUUUACAGUUCUCACAGCAAUCACUUAUCAGUAUUUAAAUUGACCUUAGCUGGGCACAGUCACUCACUUCUGUAAUCCCAGUACUUUGGGAAGCUGAGGCCAGAAGUUUAAGUCCAGCCUGGACAACAUAGCAAGACUGUUUCUACAAAAAAAAAAAUAAAAAAUUAGCCAGGUGUGGUGGCACACACCUGUAAUUCUAGCUACUUGGGAGGCUGAGGAGGGAGAAUUGCUUGAGGCUAGGAAUUCAAGGUUACAGUGGACUAUGAUUAUAACACUCCACUUCAGCUUGGGUGACAGAGCAAGACCCUGUCUCUUAAAAAAGUAAAAUAAAAUAAAUUAAUCUUUACAACAACCCUCCAAGGUAGACCAGAAAGAGGUGGUAUCCUUAUUUUAUUGAUGGUCUGUGUGAGGUCAUACAGACAGUAGGUGGCCAAGCCCAGAUGCCAAGCCUAAGCCUCGUUCCUUUUGUUUACCCAAGGUUCCUAUUCAUACCAUUAUAUGACCAUUUAGCCUUAAAUAAUCUGUUUUAAUUGCAAAUUUUAUUUUAAGAAAGGAAAAAAAUCACAUUUAUUCUGCUGCAUCUUCUUGCUUUAUUCAUAAUGAAUUCUGCAGGUCAAUUUAUCCUCAACGAUGGCAAGCCAGAAUUUAAGUAAAGCUUCUACUUAGCUGGUACAUUUGCAUGUCAAAUCUUUAAUUCAGCUGUCAGUGUUUUAGCAUUUACUGUACUUUCAUUAAUAAAUGUUAUUUUGAUGGUCUCAGGCUAAUCAAGACUAUUUGAAAUGGGGGACGGCACCAAAUGAAAUUUACAGAGAAAUCAGAGCUUCUUCAUGGACUUUAAAAUAAUUGUUACUUUACACGUGUUUGAAAUCAGAAUACUUGUAAAAUUAAAGUUAGACAUGUUGUUCUUGCAUAAACAAGCAAAAGAAGCUAAGGAAUCAACUUAGAUUUAUUUGUUCCUUUAAGAGCAUGUACUGAGCACCUGCUGUGUGCUAGACAUGUUGUAGAUAGAGGAAAUGCGGAUAUCAACAUGGCAGGCAAAAAUAACCUGCCCUCAAGAAUUUCCAUUCUAGAGCGAGUAGACAGAUGAUAUCUCAGAUAGUGCCAGGGCCUAUGGAAAAAGCUGACCAGGCAGGGCACUGAAUUCUGGGGAGUGGGUGGUCAGGGAAGGCCUUGCUUCCUUCUCAUCCACAUUCUGGCAUAGAAGUUUGAUUUCCAUGUACAUGUUUUUUUUUGUAACAUAUAGCUCCAGAAUACGUUAUUUUUAACUUUGCACUCAAUAAAAAAUCAACUUGUAGUAA